GCUCUAUCCUCGCGUCUGCUCCCAGCUCCGGGCUCCCGGGGCUGAGGUGGAGCCGCGGGACGCCGGCAGGGUUGUGGCGCAGCAGUCUCCUUCCUGCGCGCGCGCCUGAAGUCGGCGUGGGCGUUUGAGGAAGCUGGGAUACAGCAUUUAAUGAAAAAUUUAUGCUUAAGAAGUAAAAAUGGCAGGCUUCCUAGAUAAUUUUCGUUGGCCAGAAUGUGAAUGUAUUGACUGGAGUGAGAGAAGAAAUGCUGUGGCAUCUGUUGUCGCAGGUAUAUUGUUUUUUACAGGCUGGUGGAUAAUGAUUGAUGCAGCUGUGGUGUAUCCUAAGCCAGAACAGUUGAACCAUGCCUUUCACACAUGUGGUGUAUUUUCCACAUUGGCUUUCUUCAUGAUAAAUGCUGUAUCCAAUGCUCAGGUGAGAGGUGAUAGCUAUGAAAGCGGCUGUUUAGGAAGAACAGGUGCUCGAGUUUGGCUUUUCAUUGGUUUCAUGUUGAUGUUUGGGUCACUUAUUGCUUCCAUGUGGAUUCUUUUUGGUGCAUAUGUUACCCAAAAUACUGAUGUUUAUCCGGGACUAGCUGUGUUUUUUCAAAAUGCACUUAUAUUUUUUAGCACUCUGAUCUACAAAUUUGGAAGAACCGAAGAGCUAUGGACCUGAGAUCACUUCUUAAGUCACAUUUUCCUUUUGUUAUAUUCUGUUUGUAGAUAGGUUUUUUAUCUCUCAGUACACAUUGCCAAAUGGAGUAGAUUGUACAUUAAAUGUUUUGUUUCUUUACAUUUUUAUGUUCUGAGUUUUGAAAUAGUUUUAUGAAAUUUCUUUAUUUUUCAUUGCAUAGACUGUUAAUAUGUAUAUAAUACAAGACUAUAUGAAUUGGAUAAUGAGUAUCAGUUUUUUAUUCCUGAGAUUUAGAACUUGAUCUACUCCCUGAGCCAGGGUUACAUCAUCUUGUCAUUUUAGAAGUAACCACUCUUGUCUCUCUGGCUGGGCACGGUGGCUCAUGCCUGUAAUCCCAGCACUUUGGGAGGCCGAGGCGGGCCGAUUGCUUGAGGUCAAGUGUUUGAGACCAGCCUGGCCAACAUGGCGAAACCCCAUCUACUAAAAAUACAAAAAUUAGCCAGGCAUGGUGGUGGGUGCCUGUAAUCCCAACUACCUAGGAGGCUGAGGCAGGAGAAUCGCUUGAACCCGGGGGGCAGAGGUUGUAGUGAGCUGAGUUUGCGCCACUGCACUCUAGCCUGGGGGAGAAAGUGAAACUCCCUCUCAAAAAAAAGAAGGACCACUCUCAGUAUCUGAUUUCUGAAGAUGUACAAAAAAAUAUAGCUUCAUAUAUCUAGAAUGAGCACUGAGCCAUAAAAGGUUUUCAGCAAGUUGUAACUUAUUUUGGCCUAAAAAUGAGGUUUUUUUGGUAAAGAAAAAAUAUUUGUUCUUAUGUAUUGAAGAAGUGUACUUUUAUAUAAUGAUUUUUUAAAUGCCCAAAGGACUAGUUUGAAAGCUUCUUUUAAAAAGAAUUCCUCUAAUAUGACUUUAUGUGAGAAGGGAUAAUACAUGAUCAAAUAAACUCAGUUUUUUAUGGUUACUGUAAAAAGACUGUGUAAGGCAGCUCAGCACCAUGCUUCUCGUAAAAGCAGCUUCAAAUAUCCACUGGGGUUAUCUUUUGACAACUUGCCAUUAUCUGAUGUUACACAAUUCAAUAGCAAGCAAGUUUGAGACAAUCGCAGUUUAAAAGCAUGAACCAUUUAACAAAAAGUGGAAUAAUUAAAGAUAAAGCACUUCUUCCCAAAGGGAAUUAUCACCUAGUGAAAAAUUAUGCAUUUCAUCUACUCAGUUACCGACUGCAAGUCUCUCCUCGCUCUAGCUCUCAAGCUUUGGGUGAAUAUUCCUGUGAAAUAUAUCUUCAACUUGAAAGUUCAUACUCCAAUCAAAAACUCCUUUUACUGAGUUUGCAGUACUGUAUUUGCACUGUUUGUAUUCCUCUGGGCCCUUAUUGCUACUUUUGCUUUCCUUUGUUACACAGAUUUUGUGUUGCACUUUUUCUCCAGAGGGGUGUUGUAGAGCCUUGGUUGUAUGAAUAAUACCAGUGGUAGUGUCCACGGCUCUAAUGUAAGCCCAUUUGGCAUCACUCCUCUCCUCUCUCUUGAGAGGAUUUCUUGUGCACAGAGUAUGAAGCAGUUGUGGAGCGCUGUGCCUUUGUCAAGAUACCAUCUUGUUUGAUGACUUCUUUCUUUGCUGUUUUUUCUUCAAAAUGUUAGUAAGCUCUGUCAUGCUUCUAGCAAAUUGUAAGACUAAUUAUUUGUUUCCACCUCAUAACCUGUUGCAAUAAAUAUUACUUCUCAUACAGUUUAAUAUUGUUGUUUGUUGGAGAAAAUGAACCAUAAAAAUUGAUUUGCUGUUCAGUUUUCAAUUAUUCAAGUAUACCCAAUUAAAGAUGCAGUUAUGUUUAUAAAAUAAGAAGAAAUAGACUUGUAAAAUGCUUAUGUGAGGGUUAUUGAAGGUUUCCCUGAAGACUGACUGGAAAUGGUGGCUGUUUUUUUCUAUUUCUGACUCUGCCAUGAAUUUUUUUUUUUUUUUUUAAAGACAAUAUCUCACUCUGUUGCCUAGGCUGGAGUGCAGUGGUGCAACCACAGCUCACUGCACCUUCAAAUGCUGGAGCUCAGGCAAUCCUCUUACCUCCGCUUUCCAAGCAGCUGGGACCACAGAUGUAUCCUCCACUCCUCGCUGGCCACCAUCCUGCUGCCCAACAGAAGAAGCUCUUCUGUCUCCGAUUUCCUGAACGGUCUAAGGGAGCCAGUGGGCUAGGCCCAUGCUUUGGUUCAAAGCGUUUGGAGAACAUCUUCUUGCUCCUUUUCCGGAAACGAGAUAAUGGACACAGAGUCCCAGACGUCAUCCUUUGGACCAGGAAGAAACAGGCUCCUGCCAGCACCGACAGCAACGAAAAUGUUCCCACGGAGAUCAGGAUGACUUGCUGAAGCUCAGUGGAGGCUAAAAAGAGGACACGAAAGUGAACAGAAUGAUCUUCCUACGCACAACACAAACAUCAGUUAAUGUUCCAUCCAUGCUGCUUAAAGAGCAUUCCUGUCCUAGUAAAAUGGGCAAGUCCCUCUACCCCCCACCCUCACCUGGUAUGCUUACAUUAAUAGCUAAAGUCAAUCCUGUAAUGAAAUAAAGCAAGUGGUAGCUGUCUGGUAGCCUCCACUACUGCAAAUCUCA